GCAUUUUCUUCAACCAGGAGGUGAGGAGGUUUCGACAUGGCGGUGCAGCCGAAGGAGACGCUGCAGUUGGAGAGCGCGGCCGAGGUCGGCUUCGUGCGCUUCUUUCAGGGCAUGCCGGAGAAGCCGACCACCACAGUGCGCCUUUUCGACCGGGGCGACUUCUAUACGGCGCACGGCGAGGACGCGCUGCUGGCCGCCCGGGAGGUGUUCAAGACCCAGGGGGUGAUCAAGUACAUGGGGCCGGCAGGAGCAAAGAAUCUGCAGAGUGUUGUGCUUAGUAAAAUGAAUUUUGAAUCUUUUGUAAAAGAUCUUCUUCUGGUUCGUCAGUAUAGAGUUGAAGUUUAUAAGAAUAGAGCUGGAAAUAAGGCAUCCAAGGAGAAUGAUUGGUAUUUGGCAUAUAAGGCUUCUCCUGGCAAUCUCUCUCAGUUUGAAGACAUUCUCUUUGGUAACAAUGAUAUGUCAGCUUCCAUUGGUGUUGUGGGUGUUAAAAUGUCCGCAGUUGAUGGCCAGAGACAGGUUGGAGUUGGGUAUGUGGAUUCCAUACAGAGGAAACUAGGACUGUGUGAAUUCCCUGAUAAUGAUCAGUUCUCCAAUCUUGAGGCUCUCCUCAUCCAGAUUGGACCAAAGGAAUGUGUUUUACCCGGAGGAGAGACUGCUGGAGACAUGGGGAAACUGAGACAGAUAAUUCAAAGAGGAGGAAUUCUGAUCACAGAAAGAAAAAAAGCUGACUUUUCCACAAAAGACAUUUAUCAGGACCUCAACCGGUUGUUGAAAGGCAAAAAGGGAGAGCAGAUGAAUAGUGCUGUAUUGCCAGAAAUGGAGAAUCAGGUUGCAGUUUCAUCACUGUCUGCGGUAAUCAAGUUUUUAGAACUCUUAUCAGAUGAUUCCAACUUUGGACAGUUUGAACUGACUACUUUUGACUUCAGCCAGUAUAUGAAAUUGGAUAUUGCAGCAGUCAGAGCCCUUAACCUUUUUCAGGGUUCUGUUGAAGAUACCACUGGCUCUCAGUCUCUGGCUGCCUUGCUGAAUAAGUGUAAAACCCCUCAAGGACAAAGACUUGUUAACCAGUGGAUUAAGCAGCCUCUCAUGGAUAAGAACAGAAUAGAGGAGAGAUUGAAUUUAGUGGAAGCUUUUGUAGAAGAUGCAGAAUUGAGGCAGACUUUACAAGAAGAUUUACUUCGUCGAUUCCCAGAUCUUAACCGACUUGCCAAGAAGUUUCAAAGACAAGCAGCAAACUUACAAGAUUGUUACCGACUCUAUCAGGGUAUAAAUCAACUACCUAAUGUUAUACAGGCUCUGGAAAAACAUGAAGGAAAACACCAGAAAUUAUUGUUGGCAGUUUUUGUGACUCCUCUUACUGAUCUUCGUUCUGACUUCUCCAAGUUUCAGGAAAUGAUAGAAACAACUUUAGAUAUGGAUCAGCAUUUCCUGUGGAUUAGUUCACUACUUAUUUUCUUAUCUGUGGAAAACCAUGAAUUCCUUGUAAAACCUUCAUUUGAUCCUAAUCUCAGUGAAUUAAGAGAAAUAAUGAAUGACUUGGAAAAGAAGAUGCAGUCAACAUUAAUAAGUGCAGCCAGAGAUCUUGGCUUGGACCCUGGCAAACAGAUUAAACUGGAUUCCAGUGCACAGUUUGGAUAUUACUUUCGUGUAACCUGUAAGGAAGAAAAAGUCCUUCGUAACAAUAAAAACUUUAGUACUGUAGAUAUCCAGAAGAAUGGUGUUAAAUUUACCAACAGCAAAUUGACUUCUUUAAAUGAAGAGUAUACCAAAAAUAAAACAGAAUAUGAAGAAGCCCAGGAUGCCAUUGUUAAAGAAAUUGUCAAUAUUUCUUCAGGCUAUGUAGAACCAAUGCAGACACUCAAUGAUGUGUUAGCUCAGCUAGAUGCUGUUGUCAGCUUUGCUCACGUGUCAAAUGGAGCACCUGUUCCAUAUGUACGACCAGCCAUUUUGGAGAAAGGACAAGGAAGAAUUAUAUUAAAAGCAUCCAGGCAUGCUUGUGUUGAAGUUCAAGAUGAAAUUGCAUUUAUUCCUAAUGACGUAUACUUUGAAAAAGAUAAACAGAUGUUCCACAUCAUUACUGGCCCCAAUAUGGGAGGUAAAUCAACAUAUAUUCGACAAACUGGGGUGAUAGUACUCAUGGCCCAAAUUGGGUGUUUUGUGCCAUGUGAGUCAGCAGAAGUGUCCAUUGUGGACUGCAUCUUAGCCCGAGUAGGGGCUGGUGACAGUCAAUUGAAAGGAGUCUCCACGUUCAUGGCUGAAAUGUUGGAAACUGCUUCUAUCCUCAGGUCUGCAACCAAAGAUUCAUUAAUAAUCAUAGAUGAAUUGGGAAGAGGAACUUCUACCUACGAUGGAUUUGGGUUAGCAUGGGCUAUAUCAGAAUACAUUGCAACAAAGAUUGGUGCUUUUUGCAUGUUUGCAACCCAUUUUCAUGAACUUACUGCCUUGGCCAAUCAGAUACCAACUGUUAAUAAUCUACAUGUCACAGCACUCACCACUGAAGAGACCUUAACUAUGCUUUAUCAGGUGAAGAAAGGUGUCUGUGAUCAAAGUUUUGGGAUUCAUGUUGCAGAGCUUGCUAAUUUCCCUAAGCAUGUAAUAGAGUGUGCUAAACAGAAAGCCCUGGAACUUGAGGAGUUUCAGUAUAUUGGAGAAUCGCAAGGAUAUGAUAUCAUGGAACCAGCAGCAAAGAAGUGCUAUCUGGAAAGAGAGCAAGGUGAAAAAAUUAUUCAGGAGUUCCUGUCCAAGGUGAAACAAAUGCCCUUUACUGAAAUGUCAGAAGAAAACAUCACAAUAAAGUUAAAACAGCUAAAAGCUGAAGUAAUAGCAAAGAAUAAUAGCUUUGUAAAUGAAAUCAUUUCACGAAUAAAAGUUACUACGUGAAAAAUCCCAGUAAUGGAAUGAAGAACCUCAGAGUGACAGAGCCAAAAGACCAGUGCCUCAUUUUGCUGACAUGGAAAAGGAAACUUCGUGGGGGAAAGAGAUCUGCUUGCAGUCGGCCAGAGAGACAGAACCAGGGCAGUGGUGAGCUCUCAUGACCUGGUGUCUGUUGCCUUCUGGUUAAGUUUUUCAUUUGUAAUUCUACAAACAUCCCUUCUGUAAACAUUUCCCUCAAAAUGGAGCAGGAAGCUCUCAAAAAUGGACCAGAAAGGGGUCAGGAAUAUAACUUUCUCUGCCCAGAUUCCAGGACUUACAGUGAGAAAGCGCCUUCUGGGAACUUCACAAUGGCUAAAGUGUGCUAAUGGGAUGAUGUGCCCUUGUACACCCACUGCCUCUGAACUCUGCUCUGCAUUGCUGAGCAAACUACAUUUCCCAGAACUCCUUGUUGGAUUCCUUCCAAACAGGUUUACCACUGGGAGAGCCUGUUGGUUGGGGAGGGCAGGAAGAGGGAGGAAAGAGGAAGGGACUCACUUCCUGUUUCCAGCUGAAGUCUAAAUCAAUCCACUAUCAACAGGUAGCUAUCAUACUACCCUCAUUGUCACCCCUCAGAGGUCCCACUGCAGCUGCAUAAUGUCCCCUCAGUGGCCUGAACAUGAGAUGAACAACACUCUUCUUGGGAGUACCAGCCUUGCUUGGUUCAUGGCCACUUUUCCUGAUUAUCUUGCAGCUAUAUUAGGUCAUGUGACAAAGUUCUGGCCAGUGGCAAGGGAACACAAGUGAUAGGUACAGAUAGAAGUGUCUGAUACUACAUAGAUUAUGCUUGCACUCACUCUUAAGAGAGAGACAUGAACUUUUACCAACGGAAGCCAGUAUUAUUUUGAACCUCUGUUAGAGUGGCUUGAAUCUGUAUCCUAACUUGUAUCCCUAAUGUGUGACCCAUGAAAAUUAGCCAGGCAGCACCAGUUCCAAAGAAGCUCACACUCCCCUGCGGCUGCUUCUGCCAAGGUCACUGAUAUUUCCCUUUGCUAAAUCUUGUGGGUGUUUUCUUCAGUCCUUGUCUUAAUCACUCAGUGGCACUUGGCACUUAUUCCUUCUUGAAACCCUUGUUUCCCUUGGCUUUGUGGCAUCCUGUGCUCUUGGUUUUCUCCCAUAUCUCUGACCCUCUUUCCUUAGUCUUUUUUCUUCUUCCUCCUGUCCCUUAAAUGCUGGUUGUGAUCCUCUUUUUAUCUCAUUCUACACACUCACAGCCUGAGUAAUUCACACCAUCUUGAUGCUGAGAACUUCCAAAAUGUUGGUCUAGCCUGGGUCAUUGUUAUGAGCUCUAGACUCACAAGGCCAAUUGCUUGGUGGGAACCCCUCCCCCAUGGUUAUCUCAUGGGUCCCUGAAGUCCAACUUCUCCUUCAUUGAACUCAUCACCUCUUCUGUUCCUCCUCCUGGGUUCCCAGGCUCAGUGGUGGCACCACUGUCUACCUGGCUGCUUAGCCUGAGACCUGGCUCCGUCCCAAUUCCUCUCUCUCAGUCUUAUCAUCCCCAUCCAGGCAAAUCAUUGAUUCUGUGGACCUACUCUUUCGGGUGUCCCUCAAAUCUCUCCACGUCUCUGUGUUCUCACUAGCACUACCUUGGUCCACCCUGCCAUCUGCUUUCCUCCUCCACUCCUGCAUUCUGAGUCAUUUUCGGCAGCACACGCAUCCUUAAAACCCCUCCACUGGCUUGCCAGUGUCCUCAGGAUUAGGCGAAAAGUCUUUGCUUUGUUUUACAAGGCCCUUCGCUAUCUGGCCCCCUCAUUACCUCCCUUGCUCUGCAUGCUCCAGUCCUGCAGAACUACACACAGUUCCCCCAACAAGGCCCUGCUCUGUUCUUCCCACACACUGCUCCUCUGCCUGGGCCACUCUUCCUGCUCCUUGUCAGCAGGCUUGCUGCUCUCAGGCUCAGCAUGGACAGCUGCUUCUGAGAGCCUUCUCUGCCUACCCAGGCUGGGUGGCUGCCUCUCUUUGGUGUGCCCAUGGCAGCCCAGAAUGCCUGGUGGACAGGGAGCCCUCAGCAGGCCGUACUGCAGCGCCCUGCCCCCGUCAGCCUCCAGGAGCCUGGAGUCCAGGGACAUCAAGGGCGGUCCUGUCUUUCUCACCCUUGUCUCUCCAGCCCCUAACACAGGGGAUGCCUGACCCCAAACUAGACGAGUUACUUGACCUCUCUGACCCAAGACAAAAUGGGAGGAAAGUGCCAAAUUUCCAAGAUUGGCCAGGGGAUUAAAUAAGAUAAAUAUGCAAGUCUCUUAUCUGGGGGUCUGGCUUGGUAAAUAUAAAGUUCUUUUUUCUUUUCUUCCUUUUUCUUUUUUUUUUUUCUUUCUUUUUGAGACAGGGUCUUACUCUGUCACCAAGGCUGGAGUGCAGUGGCAUGAUCAUGGCUCAAUGAAACAUCGACUUCCUGGGCUCAGGCGAUCCUCCCACCUCAGCCCCCUGAGUCUCUUGGACUCCAGGCGUGCACCACCAUGACUGGCUAAUUUUUUGUAUUUUUAGUAAAGACAGGGUUUCGACAUGUUGCCUAGGCUGGUCUCGAACUCCUAGGCUAAAGUGAUCCACUUGUCUCAGCCUCCCAAAGUGCUGGGAUUAUAGACAUGAGCCACCAUGCCCAGCUAAAAGUUCCUUUUUAAAAUCUGCUUGUUAGAUACACUCAUAGAAAGGUAACUGGCCACAGAAGGGAGAGGAAUGGCAGUCCAUCCAGGGAUCACUGGAGUGUCAUAUGAAAUGUUAUAGGAAUCACAGGCCUUAGAACUUGAAAGGAACCCAAGGAUCAUCUAGGCUACUUUAUGCAGGUAAAACAGCCACCUGUGCCCAUCACAUAGCUGGGGCACAGCUGGAGACCCCAACAGAGAGGAGAGCUGAUGGGUGACGAGAAAUCAGGCCUCUCCGCCACGGCAGCCUAGCUAAUGGGUCUUGGCUGGAAGCUAACAGGAAGGCCUCUUUCCAGAAACACUGUAAGCCAGUGUUUCUCAGAUUGCUGGGUGUAAUUCAUAGGCAGAUCAUGAAAUCAGUUUAAUAGCUUUGACCAGCAUUAACCUAUUUAUGCCUAGCGUUCCCUUAUUGGAACACUAAGUCUGUGAGAGUUAUUUACAUCCUACUGCUUAAGGUCAUCGCCAAAAUCUGAUUUUUUACACAAAAAAUUUGCAACCUCCAGCAUAAAUGGGUUAAAACAAGACAAAACAAAACAAUACCAGAAUGGAAAAUAGUGCAUGAUCUGUACAGUAUAGUUGUAGAAAACUUCUUGUUUUAUCAUUUGAUGUCAUGAAAGUCCCUGCUGUAGAUAAAAGAUGGAGCUUGUGCUUCUGAGUGGUCAUGCUCAACAGGGUGGGGAGCCCAGGGGAGUGGGGAGUGAUCGUAUAGACAGAGGUGGGUGGGGCCAGUGUGAGCCUGAUGGUCAAUUACUUCUCAUUUCUAGGGAAAAUUGAAGGAAAAGAAGGAGGGGGAUGUGGAGGGGAGAGAAGGCCUCAGUAGAGUUUGCACUAUUAUUAGGGCAAGUAAGCUGCUUCUGAAAAGAAGGGGUUUGCAAAGCCAACCCAGGCAAAAGCAAUCUGCUGGAAGAACUUCAUCCCCAGCUGACACUGUGGGAAGGACCCCAUGCAGAAGCAAUAGGGCAGCCUGGUCCCAUAUCCUCAUGAAAUGCCUCUUAUAAUUGUGACAUCUUGCAAUUGUGGAGGACUUUACACUUUUCGGAGUUCCUAGCCCCUCACUUAUUUCUCGUAAGACCGCUGGGAGGUGGGGGGAUGGUAUCAUCAUCCCACUUUAGAGAUGAGGAAACAGGAUCAGAGUGAGCUAAAUGACUGCCAGAUCCAAAACUAGAAUUCAGACCUCCUAGUUUCUAAGUGGACGCUCUUUCUACACCACCAUAAUGUGAGUGUUCUGUGUUUACAGGGUGUAUUCAAGUCCAUGACUGCCCAUUAGAAUCCCCCCAAAAAAUUCCAGGACUGGCCUGAGUUGCUCCUUAGACCAAUGAAAUCAGACUCCUGGGAGUACGGCCCGGGCCUCGGGAUCCUUUAAAGCUCCAUUUGGAGAGCCUCGGGCACAGCCAGGUUGGAUCCAUCUCCCAGUCCCCCAGCCUUGGCUCAGCCUGGCCAAGCUGCCCAGGAGGUCCCUUGGUGCCCUGGGCUCUGUUUCACUGUUGUUUUGUAGAGCAACUUCCCAGUGAUGCUGCCACUGGGCCCCAUCCUAACAGUGAAGUCCCCCGGGCCCUCCUGAGAGGAGGUGUGAACUGGAAGAUGGGGAGGCAGGCGGCUCUGACAGACAGAAAGCAAACAGCUCAGAGGGGUGGCAGGCUGCAUUUUAUUCAUCGUUAAUUUAAACACCCUUCAAGUCCUCUCUUGGAAUGCUGCUCAGAAAAAUAGAUGUAUUGUUUGAGAAACCCUGCAGGCUUGUCCCGCAUGCUCUAGCCCCCUCCUGAGAGAACAGAUAGCAUAAAAAAUGAUUUGUAAAGCAAGGGGGAGCUUCCUUAGGGAAGAAGGGGAAGGGGAAGAGGGUUUGGGGCCAGGUCCGAGUGCAGAAAUCCUCAAUGCAUGAGACUAGCGUGGAAGGUGUAGCAAUUGUGCUCUGGGGUGCCUGAAAGUGCCAGAGCUGCUUCAGGGGCAAGAGUCCAGGCCCCAAGUCCAUGCUGAUGAGCCCACCCUGGGGGUCAGGAAUGGCCUCAGCAGGCCCUCCCUCCCUCCCUCUCCACCCUACAAAGUGAGGAGCCUUGAGUCACCACCAGCACAUUAUACAACAAUACAAGAACCCUGCAACAGAUAAAGCCCCAGCGCCUCUUCUGGACUCAGAUGCCCUAGGCUGGCUGUCUGGCUGUGCUUUCCAGACAGUGUGUAUGUGGAAUUGUGCUUUUUGUUUUUUAAGAAUGUAAAAAGUUACAGUAAGAUCGAACCACAGGGCCCGUCGCUCCUAUGGUCUCUGCCUGACUGGGCUGCCGUCUGCCUCAGUUCCCCAGAAGCUUCUCCUUUGGCCAUGAGGGCUCAGUCAUCCCUCACCCCAGAGUCCACAGGAAGAGGGGGUCUGCUGGGAGGCCUGUCUGAAGGACGGAGGAUCCUGGGUCAAUUUAGCAGCUAUUUUCCAGGGUUUGGCUUGGGUUUGGAUGCUGGCUUCUGUGUGAAACCUGAAUACAUGCAAAUUGUACAUAAAACUCCCCCAAGGCAGAGAGGGAUUUUCCAGGCCCUGGUACAUCUCUAGAGAGUUAAAAAUGGGAAAUCUUUCUUCUUAAAGUGGCCCAGACUGAGACUUUUCCUUGGGGAAAAGGGUUAGUAGCUCUUUGUAAGGCUGGUGUGUAUGUGUGUGUGUAUAUAUAUAUACAUAUAUGCAUGAUGCUGUGCAAAUGCCCAGGGCUGUCUGGCAUUUUCCACAAAAUGAGAGCCUGAGAUUGCCUAAGCCUUCUGAUGCCUUCUCCAGGCCUGGAGGCACUGCUUCAUUCAGAGGACACAAAGGCCUGACCACCUGGCUUUAGCAAGCUAGGACACCCAGGGUGGCUUCUUUACCUUUCUCCUCAGCUCUGAGAAGGCUGCUAGCCAAGACUCUGGAUUCUCUGUGGCCACAGUCAUAUGGUGAGGGCCUCUUGGAGUUCAUUCAAACUUUAAGGGAGCCCCACAGCACCGGCAUGAUGGGUAAGUCCAGGCCUAAGGUUAGGAAGCAAAUCCUGGAGCAUGAGGAAAUUGUAGGCUACAGUGAGCUACCAGUGGUGUGCAAACUGGAGACCCCCAAGACAGUGAGAGAGGCCACAGCAUCUGAGGGAAUGGAGCUCUUUCUUGGCCUGAGGUUCAGAAGAACCUGCACCAAAGAAAGGCAUCCCUAUCAAUGUCACUGUUCCUGAAAUGAUGGGAGAACCACAUCCCUGCUUCAGGGAAGCAGUCCCUGUCGUCUGGGGCGCUGAGCCCUUUGGCCUGAGAUGAAGGAUGAUGGUGUGAUGUAUCAUGGCAGUGUGACUGAGACUGGAUUGGGGGAUGGGGACAGGGGAACAUAGGCAAAAAUACACAUGUGCCACUGGAUCCUGAGCUGCCAUUGUACCUUGGAGGACUGGCGUUUCUCUGGGAAGUUGGGAGGUGGGAAGAGGAAGGGUCUCAUUUUCCUGCCCCUUGAAACCAUGCUUACCAUUCCUUUAGAAGAUUGCUCAAGCUGCCUCCAAUUGCCUCUUUCCAAAACCAAAGCAUAGGAAAACAAGUAAAAACAGCUGAGGCUGCAGCAUAAGCAACUUAGGAUAGAGUCUAGGAAGCACCGCCAACAGAGAAGACUGCCAAGAAACAUUUUGAGUUUUUCUUCUCUGGAGGUGGGUCCUGGUUCCUCCCAUGGAGACCACGAUUCUGUGUAGUCCUGCACGCUGGGCGGGGGAUUGCCUGGAGGUUUCUUUAGACCUGUCUAGCUCACACAGUCUUGAUGCCUGGGUUUUAGGCUGCUGUACUGUUGCUGGGGCUCACUUCCUGUGGGUAGGCUGUUAUUUUGCCCGCAGAUCAAGUCCUCACUGUCUAGAUGCCUCUAUCAUGGGGAUCUCUUCUUCCCUCUCUGGAUGGCUCUGAUCCCCAAGUUAUUUCCUGUUGCCUAGGUAACACCUCUAAUUGGAUGCCUUUUAAUCGUUCCCUUUUUUAAAGGGAUAAAUGUGGAUUUUAUUUCCAGGUCCUGUCAGAGGGCCCUGCCCUAGAGAACACGUGCGCCCCUGCGUGGGCAAUCCCUUCACUGUGACCGCAACCAUGGGUUGGAUGGGGGGCACUCACUGGGCUGGCCUGACAGUCACAGUGAAUCCUGAAAGCAUGGUUUUCACAGGAACCCACCUUCAGGAUUUAGCAAGACUGACGUCUCUCCUGGCCAGCGCUGCUUCACUGGCUUCACCCCAGAUUAGGGCCUGUGUUUAAAAACCAAUCCCAACUCAAAUCAGAAAUUACCCAAAAUAGCUGGAGAGUCACUGAGAUCUCAGGUAAGCUUUCCCUUCCUGCCAUGAACUAGAAGGGGAAAGAAGAGUUUGACAUUCAAGUUUGACUCUAAUGCUGGGUGCGUGAGCGCAUGCGUGCAUGUUUGUGUGUGUGUGUGUUCCACGCACAUUUGCCAGGGAGAGAGAUUUCACAGCAUGGCUCCAGCUGGAGGCGGUGAGGCGGUGCUUUUCUAAGACUUCCUAUCAGAAGCUGUGCAUACUGGUGGGUCACGCCGUGCCUGUAUAAACUCUGGCACCUGUCCUUGCCCUCAUCAUAUAUGAGAAAAAUGGGCAGAGAGAGUGUUCGUUUACACCCCCAGACCACUAUCCUUUCAAUGAAGCCUGGGUAUCUGGCCUUCCUCCAGGUCAGGGACCCCCUAUGCUGCAGAAGGCAAGUCUGGGAGAAUCUGUCCCUCAGCCCGAGAGCAAAACUGUAAUCCUAACAUUACUUCCAUCCACCAGUUUCACCAGCUACCUCCCUCCUGCCUUCCUCUGCCUCCAAUAGGCUGUGCAUGGAGAAGACAAAUCCUCUUGAUAAACAAUAUUUAGAAAGGGAUUCUAUCUUUCCUGACCCCAAACACAUCAUGGCCUCUGGAGCCAAAUACCCUGACAUUUGCAAGAUGGCUUCUUUUGGGUUCCUGGUGCUGCAGGCCCUGGUUCCCAAGGACGCAGCUGGCAGAGGUGCCUCCUUCAGAGGAGGAGGAGGAGAAGCUGGAGGGCUGCGCCCGGCAACCCCAUGAUCUCUUAAAGGGGGAAAAGUUGAACUGAUCAACAGUAGUUAAGAAAAAAAAAAUCCACACCAACAAAUAAAUAUCUUGUCUGAGAAGACUCA